GAGUAACGAUGCUGUCCUAGCAAGUGAUGCUGUCGGAGACAGGAGACGGGCGCCGAGGAGGCAUCGCCGCCGCCGCGGGGCUGGAGAGCCUCUCCCAGCACCAGAGCCCCGCUCGGCCCCGGGCUUCCUCGUCGCAGCCACGGCCGCGGCAGCUGCUCCCACGGUUUGAUGGUGGGCGGCGGCAGCUCGGCUUCGGCGCUAGCCUCUAACUGCUGGAUCGCGGGCCGCGACGCUCUCCGCUCCUGCCUUCCCGCCCUGGGCCGCCCGGGGCCCCGGAAGCCGCGGGAGGUGGUGAAGGGGCGCCGCGGGAAGACUGCACUGCCGCGAAGGCGGAGGAGGCCGGCAGCCGGCACCCCCACACUCGGACCGCAGCCGGCGCGAUGUCCACCAAGGUCAGGAAGUGCAAAGAACAAGCAAGGGUGACCUUCCCGGCGCCGGAGGAGGAGGAAGACGAGGGCGAGGACGAGGGCGCGGAGCCGCAGCGCCGCCGCCGGGGCUGGAGGGGCGUCAACGGGGGGCUGGAGCCGCGCUCGGCGCCCUCGCAGCGGGAGCCGCACGGCUACUGCCCGCCGCCCUUCUCCCACGGGCCGGACCUGUCCAUGGAGGGAAGCCCAUCCCUGAGACGCAUGACAGUGAUGCGGGAGAAGGGCCGGCGCCAGGCUGUCAGGGGCCCGGCCUUCAUGUUCAAUGACCGCGGCACCAGCCUCACCGCCGAGGAGGAGCGCUUCCUCGACGCCGCCGAGUACGGCAACAUCCCAGUGGUGCGCAAGAUGCUGGAGGAGUCCAAGACGCUGAACGUCAACUGCGUGGACUACAUGGGCCAGAACGCGCUGCAGCUGGCUGUGGGCAACGAGCACCUGGAGGUGACCGAGCUGCUGCUCAAGAAGGAGAACCUGGCGCGCAUUGGCGACGCCCUGCUGCUCGCCAUCAGCAAGGGCUACGUGCGCAUCGUAGAGGCCAUCCUCAACCACCCUGGCUUCGCGGCCAGCAAGCGUCUCACUCUGAGCCCCUGUGAGCAGGAGCUGCAGGACGACGACUUCUACGCUUACGACGAGGACGGCACGCGCUUCUCGCCGGACAUCACCCCCAUCAUCCUGGCGGCGCACUGCCAGAAAUACGAAGUGGUGCACAUGCUGCUGAUGAAGGGUGCCAGGAUCGAGCGGCCGCACGACUAUUUCUGCAAGUGCGGGGACUGCAUGGAGAAGCAGAGGCACGACUCCUUCAGCCACUCACGCUCGAGGAUCAAUGCCUACAAGGGGCUGGCCAGCCCGGCUUACCUCUCAUUGUCCAGCGAGGACCCGGUGCUUACGGCCCUAGAGCUCAGCAACGAGCUGGCCAAGCUGGCCAACAUAGAGAAGGAGUUCAAGAAUGACUAUCGGAAGCUCUCCAUGCAAUGCAAAGACUUUGUAGUGGGUGUGCUGGAUCUCUGCCGAGACUCAGAAGAGGUAGAAGCCAUUCUGAAUGGAGAUCUGGAAUCAGCAGAGCCUCUGGAGGUACACAGGCACAAAGCUUCAUUAAGUCGUGUCAAACUUGCCAUUAAGUAUGAAGUCAAAAAGUUUGUGGCUCAUCCCAACUGCCAGCAGCAGCUCUUGACGAUCUGGUAUGAGAACCUCUCAGGCCUAAGGGAGCAGACCAUAGCUAUCAAGUGUCUCGUUGUGCUGGUCGUGGCCCUGGGCCUUCCAUUCCUGGCCAUUGGCUACUGGAUCGCACCUUGCAGCAGGCUGGGGAAAAUUCUGCGAAGCCCUUUUAUGAAGUUUGUAGCACAUGCAGCUUCUUUCAUCAUCUUCCUGGGUCUGCUUGUGUUCAAUGCCUCAGACAGGUUCGAAGGCAUCACCACGCUGCCCAAUAUCACAGUUACUGACUAUCCCAAACAGAUCUUCAGGGUGAAAACCACCCAGUUUACAUGGACUGAAAUGCUAAUUAUGGUCUGGGUUCUUGGAAUGAUGUGGUCUGAAUGUAAAGAGCUCUGGCUGGAAGGACCUAGGGAAUACAUUUUGCAGUUGUGGAAUGUGCUUGACUUUGGGAUGCUGUCCAUCUUCAUUGCUGCUUUCACAGCCAGAUUCCUAGCUUUCCUUCAGGCAACGAAGGCACAACAGUAUGUGGACAGUUACGUCCAAGAGAGUGACCUCAGUGAAGUGACACUCCCACCAGAGAUACAGUAUUUCACUUAUGCUAGAGAUAAAUGGCUCCCUUCUGACCCUCAGAUUAUAUCUGAAGGCCUUUAUGCCAUAGCUGUUGUGCUCAGCUUCUCUCGGAUUGCGUACAUCCUCCCUGCAAAUGAGAGCUUUGGCCCCCUGCAGAUCUCUCUUGGAAGGACUGUAAAGGACAUAUUCAAGUUCAUGGUCCUCUUUAUUAUGGUGUUUUUUGCCUUUAUGAUUGGCAUGUUCAUACUUUAUUCUUACUACCUUGGGGCUAAAGUUAAUGCUGCUUUUACCACUGUAGAAGAAAGUUUCAAGACUUUAUUUUGGUCAAUAUUUGGGUUGUCUGAAGUGACUUCCGUUGUGCUCAAAUAUGAUCACAAAUUCAUAGAAAAUAUUGGAUACGUUCUUUAUGGAAUAUACAAUGUAACUAUGGUGGUCGUUUUACUCAACAUGCUAAUUGCUAUGAUUAAUAGCUCAUAUCAAGAAAUUGAGGAUGACAGUGAUGUAGAAUGGAAGUUUGCUCGUUCAAAACUUUGGUUAUCCUAUUUUGAUGAUGGAAAAACAUUACCUCCACCUUUCAGUCUAGUUCCUAGUCCAAAAUCAUUUGUUUAUUUCAUCAUGCGAAUUGUUAACUUUCCCAAAUGCAGAAGGAGAAGGCUUCAGAAGGAUAUAGAAAUGGGAAUGGGUAACUCAAAGUCCAGGUUUACAAAGUGCUUUCCUGUACAUUUGAACCUCAUGCAACGCUGUGAGUUAAACCUCUUCACUCAGUCUAACUCAAGAGUUUUUGAAUCACACAGUUUUAACAGCAUUCUCAAUCAGCCAACACGUUAUCAGCAGAUAAUGAAAAGACUUAUAAAGCGGUAUGUUUUGAAAGCACAAGUAGACAAAGAAAAUGAUGAAGUUAAUGAAGGUGAAUUAAAAGAAAUCAAGCAAGAUAUCUCCAGCCUUCGUUAUGAACUUUUGGAAGACAAGAGCCAAGCAACUGAGGAAUUAGCCAUUCUAAUUCAUAAACUUAGUGAGAAACUGAAUCCCAGCAUGCUGAGAUGUGAAUGAUGCAGCAACCUGGAUUUGGCUUUGACUAUAGCACAAAUGUGGGCAAUAAUAUUUCUAAGUAUGAAAUACUUGAAAAACUAUGAUGUAAAUUUUUAGUAUUAACUACCUUUAUCAUGUGAACCUUUAAAAGUUAGCUCUUAAUGGUUUUAUUGUUUUAUCACAUGAAAAUGCAUUUUAUUUGUCUGCUUUGACAUUACAGUGGCAUACCAUUGUGUUGAAAAGCCCAAUAUUACUAUAUUAUUGAAACUUUUAUUCAUUUUAGAGUAAACUCCACAUCUUUGCACUACCUGUUUGCCUCCAAGAGACUAUCAGUUCCUUGGGGACAGGGACCAUGUCUUAUUCAUCUUUGUGUCUCCAGCAUCUAGUACAGUGCCUGGUAUAUAGUAGGUGCUCAAUAAAUGUUGAAACCAACUGAACUGCCAACAAAAUAAAAAUAAAAAGUCUUCACUAUGUAGCAUACCUUCCCUUGUCCAAGUUCUGAAGAGGUUUUUUUUUUUUUUUUUUAAUAGAAACUGAAGACAUUUUACAACCAGCUAUGACUUGGUAAGACAUUCUUAGAAUUUUAGGUGUCACUGAUAAUCCUAGAACCACUGAGCCCCAAGUGAAGAAUUUAACAACAAAAUGGGUUAAUGAAAAAUAUAAUUACAUUGUAUAUUUAAGUUUCAUAGAAUUAUUUAAAACAACACAUUAAAGAUUUUUCUAAAAUAUAGACUGCUUGCUUUCUGUCUUAGACUUACGUUUGUUGUUUUUCAGUAAUGUGAUUUUCUUUUAAGUUGGGGGUUAUGCAGGGUUGUCAUUUUGUUAUAACCAUCUAAUUUCUGCCUCUGCUGCUUUAAUGCUAAAUGAGAUAUCAACAGCUGACUUCAUAUCUCACCUGUGAGCUCCCUGCUGAGUUUUGGAGGGUCUGCUCAUGGGAAGAAAUAGGAAAGAGCAGUGACUAUGGGCGUACUUGGAAAGACAUGGCCAAGCAUCCCCAGGUGUGUUUCAGUUCCUUUUGGGGCAUUUAUUGCCAUCGUUGCUUACAAUGAUUGACAUCUUUGUUUCUUAUCAAAGGAUUCCAGUUCCACUUUCUAUAUAAAAUAUAUUGUGAUAUAUCUACAUAUGCCUUAUUACAUAAUUGUGCUGAAUGCUGGUAAUAUCCGCAAUGCCUCUUGACUUUAAUGGGAAAAGGCAUGCAGACCAGUAAGUUCCCCAGUCACUUCAGAGACUAUAAAACACUCAAAGCAUUUUUUAACCAGCUAGGUUUAAAUCUCUCAUAGAGUUAUGUUUAACAUCCUGAGUCUGCAGUCAGUUGCUGUCAAGUCGUAUAGGAAUACGAAUUGUGAUCAUAGAUCAAAGAUUUUCAGAGGUCCUUAAAACCAACUAAAUACAUGCUACUUUAAAAUCAUUGCUAUCAUGCAGAAAAGCUCUUUAGACAUGAAGACAGAAAUAAGUGUUAAAUGGAACUACAUAAAGCUCUUUAAAGAUUAUUUCUUAAUUUCUACUUUUUGGGAGUUAAAUUAAGAAAGGAACUUUAUAAAUGUUUUGCUACCAUUGUAGAACACUUCAUUAACUUUUGUGCCAUGCUAAGAGUAUUCGUCUUAAACAUUUUUCAAACUUUAUGUACUUUAUGUUGUGUCUCAGAACUGAAUAAAAUAUUGAAUUUUUCCAUUGUUAUAUGUUACCAUAUGUUAAGAUAGUAAAGAUACAAAGUUUCUAUAAUAGAUGUUUCUGAUAGUUUUAUAGUAUGGUCCAGGAUUCCAAGUGUGAAAAGUUUUUGCUUAUAGCUAUGGAACUGAAUAUUUUGUAAUUUUCUUCUUUGCGGUUGGAAAAAAUGUUGAAUGAAAAAGUGGCAGAUUCAGCUGGGGACAUUCAGCCUAAGAUUCUUGGAAUCUGAAGAUCAGAGAAGUAUGAAGAUAAGCCUCAUGGUAUCCACACCAUGUGGAUAAAAAGCUGACUUUUUUUUUUUUUUUUUUUUGUCCAUGCCCCUCACAACUGUAGAGCUCUUAACAGGCAUUUUUUCUUUAUUUACUAUGUACAAACUGGUAUAGUUUUAAUAUUUCAUCUUUUUCCUUAUUCAUCAUUUCAAGGUGUUGUUUCAGAAGAAGGUGUGAUGACAAGGUGUAGUGAGUGUGGUUGAUGUUUUUGAUGCCCUGCCCAGAUGCCCUCUACUGGACCAGUGCACCUGUCUCCCAGAUUCUCCUGUGCAGUUCCUAGCCAAUCACUUCCCCUGGAGAAUUGCCCUCAGCUAAAAAGAAGAAGCCUUGCUCGGGAUGUGAUGCCUCCGCCUCCCCAUGGCCAGUGACUGAUGGGUGGGGGCACAAAGGGCUGGCCCCUUGUCUCAAGAUGGGGCCAACUAUUCAGUGCAGUUCAUGCUCCAGAGCUCCUGAAAGGAUUAGGGUGAUGCCAGACUCAAGCUGAGAUGAAAUCCUGGUUUAGAUUCUUCCUCUGCCUUUUCCAGUUUCCUUCCUUCCCUUUCUCCAGAGAGCAUCCCCUUAAUGAGUCACCACAUCCAAAUCUUAUUAGGUUUUGCUUUUAGGGAACUCACACUAAGCCAUAAGGUAUUAAUGUGGUAGCAUACGGUUGAGAUGAGGAUUAGUCGAGGGGAUUGCUGUCAGAAUUAGUCCUUCACUUGAGGAUAAAGAUAGCUCUGGGUCAGCAAGUCUUUUCCCUAGUCACUUUUAACAGGUACCUUUGGGAAAACAAACCUCAAAGAAGUUGUUGGGGCAACUCAGAGAAGGGAGCAUUUAAACAGGACCAAAAACAACUUUAUAGAAAAAAACAUUAAUUAAAGGAUUGUCAAAGCCCCAGGACUCUUUUUUCCUUAGGACAUCUCUCAUUUUUUACCUCUUUGCUAUUCUUAUUUUUUUCUCAUUUACAGAUAAAGAAAAGAAAGCAACACUCAAAGUGCUUCUUAGACUUAUUGUUCGAAAAGUUGGGUACUUUGUAAGUGCCUGCUGUAUUGAAUUUACAGAGCACCCAUGACUUUAUGGAAGUCACAAUCUGUUGAAAAGUUUGGGUUCUUAGACUUGAAAUAAUGAGAAAACUUUGAAAAAUGGUACAGAGUAUCUUUACAGAGUUUAUGCACAAUAAAAACAAAAAUGAUAUGUUGUGAUUAUUAAAAGCAAAUUUGGUACAAUUUAGGAUAACUAUCUUACCCAAUAUGUCAAUAUAUUUAUAUUUCAAAUGUGCAAGCCAAGUGAAAGCAGCUUUUGUAAAUGGGAAGAUAAAUUGUCUGAUGGACAAUGUCUAAAGAGAACUGAAGCCACACUAAUGACUGUGGUAUGGGACAAACCAUUUAACUUCUCUGGUCUUCAUAAAUGGUUCAGGCAAACAGGGUUAUGCUACAUCAGGGGUUCCUAGUCCCUGGAGCUCAUAGAGGUGUUUUAGGAGGUUAAUGUCAUCAUCCAAGGUGGUAAUCUUUCUUUCCAUGUCUUUUUAAAUUUUUUAAAUAAAGUUUUUAAAAUACAUUUUUAGAGGCGGGUCUCACUAUGUUGUCCAGGCUAGUCUUUAACUUUUGGCCUCAAGCGAUCCUCCUGCCUCAGCCUCCCAAAAUCAGGCUGGGCACAGUGGUGCACACCUGUAAUCGCAGCACUUUGGGACGUUGAAGCAGGUCGAUGGCUUCAGUUCAGGAGUUCGAGACCAGCAGGGCAACAUGGUGAAACUGUCUCUACAAAAAAUACAAAAAAAAUUAGCCGGGCAUGGUGGCAUGUGUCUGUGGUUCCAGUUACUCAGGAGGCUGGGGUGAGAGGAUAACUUGAGCCCAGGAAGUUGAGGCUGCAGUGAGCUGGUUCACGCCACUGCACUCCAGCCUGGGUGACAAAGUGAACCACCCCCCACAAAAAAAAAAAAAAAAAAAAAAAAAAAUCUAAAAUGGGUAUUUAUAACUUUGUUCAGUUUAAAAAAGAGUUUGAGAAUUUCUAAAUUUAUACCAUGUGUUAGGGGAAACUAAUGUUUUUACUCAUGACUCAGUCACUCAGCUGACCACCACUAGCGUGUUGAUGGUUUUAACUUUAAUGCAGUUUAAAUUGCUUUUAUUUUUAGCCAUAAGUUGUUUAACUUAUACUCAUAAUGGUUGCUUUAGCACCAUAACAUAAGGUUAUAAAUUACUGAGGUGCAUGGUAAUUCUGCAAAUUUGUCUCUAAAGUGGUCUUUGUCACAUCUGAGAGGCAGCCAUCUUCUGUUGAGUUUUAUAAAGACCACCAAGAUGUCUCUGAUACCCUAAAACAUCUUUAAAAAGAGGACACACAGUGGUAAUUUAACUUGACAUUUUCUUUAUUGUGAAUAAAAAUUCCUUACCCUGCUAAUUAAUUAUUUGAGGAAUACUUAAAAUUAGUAGGUUGAAAUCUUUACUAAUCAUUUAGAAACAAAACAUAGUAUGUACUUUAAAAAUAAUAAAUUGCAUUUUUAGAUGCAAAAUCAAAGAAUUCCAAAUAUCAUAUUAUGCAAACUUUUUGUAUUGUUUUGAUGCUAUAUCAUAGCCUCAUUUCACUGUUUUAAAAUAAAUUUGAGCUUCAAAAUAAACUUUUACUUUCCUUCUACACAAUUAAUUGAACAGUGGACAUCACUUGCUAAAUGGAAAGUAAGCACUGCCAGCAUUGUCUGUCUUUGGUGUUUUUUUUUUUACCUAUUUAUUAGAACCAUAGUAUUUCUUCAUUAUUAAUUUGUAUGAACUAUUUUUUAAGAUAUUAACUCUUUUCUCCUAUAUUUUUGUUUUCAUUUAAACAUUGUUGUGACAUAUUGAAAUGUUUAUCUUUACUUUUCAUUUUUUUUAAGUUAGUUUUUUGUUUGUUUUUUAGAGAUGGGGCCUUGCUAUUUUGCCCAGGCUGGAUUGUUGGGCUCAAGCAAUCUUGAGCCUCAGCCUUCAAAUAGCUGAGACUACAGGCAUGUAACACCAUAUCUGCUUUUUUCCUUUGUGGUUUCUUCUAUUCCUUUUGAGAUCAGUUUCCUUCUGUUAUGGGCUGAAUUGUGUCCCCUCAAAACUCAUGUUAAAGUCCUCGCCUUCAGUAUCUCAGACUAUAACUAUAGUUGGAGAUAGGGUCUUUAAAGAGGUAAUUAAUUUAAAAUGAGAUAAUAUGACUGGUGUGCUUAUAAAAAGACAAGAUGAGACACAGACAGACAUAGAGGGAGGACCACGUGAAGACACGGAGAAGAUGACGAUCUAUAAGCCAAGAAGAGAGGCCUCUGAAGAUCGGUUUUAUUCCCUGCUGACACCUUGAUCUAUGACUUCUAGACUCCAAGACUGUGAGAAAAUAAAUUUCUGUUGUUGAAAAGCC